UUAAAUUAUGGCAGAGACAAGUCUGUUAGAGGCUGGGGCCUCUGCAGCCUCUACAGCUGCGGCUUUGGAGAACUUACAGGUGGAGGCGAGCUGCUCUGUGUGCCUGGAGUAUCUGAAGGAACCUGUCAUCAUUGAGUGUGGGCACAACUUCUGCAAAGCUUGCAUCACCCGCUGGUGGGAGGACCUAGAGAGGGACUUCCCUUGUCCUGUCUGUCGAAAGACAUCCCGCUACCGCAGUCUCCGACCUAAUCGGCAACUAGGCAGUAUGGUGGAAAUUGCCAAGCAGCUCCAGGCCGUCAAGCGGAAGAUCCGGGAUGAGAGCCUCUGCCCCCAACACCAUGAGGCCCUCAGCCUUUUCUGUUAUGAGGACCAGGAGGCUGUAUGCUUGAUAUGUGCAAUUUCCCACACCCACCGGGCCCACACCGUUGUGCCACUGGACGAUGCUACACAGGAGUACAAGGAAAAACUGCAGAAGUGUCUGGAGCCCCUGGAACAGAAGCUGCAGGAGAUCACUCGCUGCAAGUCCUCUGAGGAGAAGAAGCCUGGUGAGCUCAAGAGACUAGUGGAAAGUCGCCGACAGCAGAUCUUGAGGGAGUUUGAAGAGCUUCAUAGGCGGCUGGAUGAAGAGCAGCAGGUGUUGCUUUCACGACUGGAAGAAGAGGAACAGGACAUUCUGCAGCGACUCCGAGAAAAUGCUGCUCACCUUGGGGACAAGCGCCGGGACCUGGCCCACUUGGCUGCCGAGGUGGAGGGCAAGUGCUUACAGUCAGGCUUCGAGAUGCUUAAGGAUGUCAAAAGUACCCUGGAAAAAUGUGAAAAGGUGAAGACCAUGGAGGUGACUUCAGUAUCCAUAGAGCUGGAAAAGAACUUCAGCAAUUUUCCCCGACAGUACUUUGCCCUAAGGAAAAUCCUUAAACAGCUAAUUGCGGAUGUGACCCUGGACCCUGAGACAGCUCAUCCUAACCUAGUCCUGUCAGAGGAUCGUAAGAGCGUCAAGUUCGUGGAGACAAGACUCCGGGAUCUCCCUGACACACCAAGGCGUUUCACCUUCUACCCUUGCGUCCUGGCUACUGAGGGUUUCACCUCAGGUCGACACUACUGGGAGGUGGAGGCCGCCCAUUGUGUCCUUGCCCAGGACCCCGAGAACCAGGCGCUGGCGAGGUUUUACUGCUACACUGAGAGGACCAUUGCGAAGCGGCUCGUCUUGCGGCGGGAUCCCUCGGUGAAGAGGACUCUCUGUCGAGGCUGCUCUUCCCUCCUCGUCCCGGGCCUCACCUGCACCCAGCGCCAGAGACGCUGCAGGGGACAGCGCUGGACCGUACAGACCUGCCUAACAUGCCAGCGCAGCCAACGCUUCCUCAAUGAUCCCGGGCAUUUACUCUGGGGAGACAGGCCUGAGGCCCAGCUCGGGAGCCAAGCAGAUUCCAAACCACUACAACCCUUGCCAAACACAGCCCACUCCAUUUCAGACCGCCUUCCUGAGGAGAAAAUGCAGACUCAGGGUUCCAGUAACCAGUGAUGGAUUCACCCCAUCUCCCAAAUAAAGUUUACUUGUUUUACAUUCCAU